UUAACUUUAUGAAGUGCAUCAUAAAACAACGUUUUAUUUGAAGUUGCUGAUACGGAAUUCAGAUGGGAGGACCAAUUCUUCUUGGCUACUAUUAAAUACUUUUGAAUAUCAAAUCUCAGAUUAAAUGAAGGGAAUAGUACUGGAAGAAAUAUAGAUGAAAGAAAGAAAAUGCAAGGAGAAAACUUCACCAUUUGGAGCAUUUUUUUCUUGGAGGGAUUUUCCCAGUACCCAGGGUUAGAAGUGGUUCUCUUCGUCUUCAGCCUUGUAAUGUAUCUGACAACGCUCUUGGGCAACAGCACUCUUAUUUUGAUCACUAUCCUAGAUUCACGCCUUAAAACCCCCAUGUACUUAUUCCUUGGAAAUCUCUCUUUCAUGGAUAUUUGUUACACAUCUGCCUCUGUUCCUACUUUGCUGGUGAACUUGCUGUCAUCCCAGAAAACCAUUAUCUUUUCUGGGUGUGCUGUACAGAUGUAUCUGUCCCUUGCCAUGGGCUCCACAGAGUGUGUGCUCCUGGCCGUGAUGGCAUAUGACCGUUAUGUGGCCAUUUGUAACCCGCUGAGAUACUCCAUCAUCAUGAACAGGUGCGUCUGUGCACGGAUGGCUACGGUCUCCUGGGUGACGGGUUGCCUGACCGCUCUGCUGGAAACCAGUUUUGCCCUGCAGAUACCCCUCUGUGGGAAUCUCAUCGAUCACUUCACGUGUGAAAUUCUGGCGGUGCUAAAGUUAGCUUGCACAAGUUCACUGCUCAUGAACACCAUCAUGCUGGUGGUCAGCAUUCUCCUCUUGCCAAUUCCAAUGCUCUUAGUUUGCAUCUCUUACAUCUUCAUCCUUUCCACUAUUCUGAGAAUCACCUCAGCAGAGGGAAGAAACAAGGCUUUUUCUACCUGUGGUGCCCAUUUGACUGUGGUGAUUUUGUAUUAUGGGGCUGCCCUCUCUAUGUACCUAAAGCCUUCUUCAUCAAAUGCACAAAAAAUAGACAAAAUCAUCUCGUUGCUUUACGGAGUGCUUACCCCUAUGUUGAACCCCAUAAUUUACAGUUUAAGAAACAAGGAAGUCAAAGAUGCUAUGAAGAAAUUGCUGGGCAAAAUAACAUUGCAUCAAACACACGAACAUCUCUGAUUGGGUCCCUAUGGUUUUACCAGAGAUGUGCCCCUGGCAGAGCUCAUCAGAGAAAUUCGAGACAACAUACAACCUCUUAGAACUCUGAUCGGAUCUUAUCUCUAUAUAAUUUCACAGUUAUGAGCUGCAUACACAGAGUGAUUGCCUAUUAAUAAUAGUAGGUUUCAAUUUGCAUUUGUUAAUAUUUCCUUUUUGUGUUUUGUGGUUGUGAGGUUUUGAGUUAUAGAGUCAUUAAAUGUUUGCUACAGAAGAAA